CUUUCAUUUCAGAGUUGAGCAAACUGUGUCUCAAGGAGGUGUGCGCUGCAGGUAGCUGAUGUGGCCAGGAUUUGAACCCACAUUUUAUAUUCUUUGCCAUUAGAUUCCAUUUUUCUUAUCUCUUAUUUCUCAGCGCCAGGUCUCUUUUUGUUUCUGGGCCUCUUUCUUCCUUGGCCUCCUGCCUCCCUGUCUUCCCAUGUUCUUGUAUCUGCUGCUGCCUGUGUUUUUCUCAUUGUGUCUCUGCCUAGCUCCCUCUGCCCAGGUUUCUAUGUGUCUCUUUCUGUCAGAACUGUCUUCUAUUUCUUCUCAGUCCCCUUCUCUGCAUUUGUUACAUCAUCUCUUCAUCUUAAUGUAUUAGGCUGGGGCUGUUUUGGGACUCCAGAGAGUUACUUUUUAACUAGCUACAUCUGUCUUCAGGUGCCUGGCUUUCUGGCCUGAGGUGGAAGCAGAGGCCAGCCUCUCUCCGUCAUCCCUAUCUCCCCUGGGCUUACAUCAUGGCGGGGCUUUGAAAAUCUCCCUCUGUGGCUUCUUGGAGCCGCAUAGAUGGGUGAUCAGAGCUGGCUCUGGAACCAGGCUGCUCCAGGAGUAAGGAGCCCAGUCUUUGCAUGCAGUGUUGAAAAAGGUAAUGUCCCUCUUGUGCUGAGCGAGCACCUGGCACACAGCAGGGACCCAGGCAGUGGGGCUGUUAGGUUCCUUAUCUCUCCUGAGCCUUGGGCUUCCGCUAUCCUUGGGACGUCUGGUCUUCUGGCUUCCCCGGUUCUUCCUGCCGCCCUGGAUGCGGUGACCUGCCAGCACCUGCCGCAGCCUUCGUCCGGGAGUCGCCCCAUCUCUCCACGCAUCGGGGCCCUGUGCCCCUUGCUGCUGCAGCCGGGCACCAUGUCGACCUCGUCCUUGAGGCGCCAGAUGAAGAACAUCGUCCACAACUACUCAGAGGCGGAGAUCAAGGUUCGAGAGGCCACGAGCAAUGACCCCUGGGGCCCAUCCAGCUCCCUCAUGUCAGAGAUUGCCGACCUCACCUACAACGUUGUCGCCUUCUCGGAGAUCAUGAGCAUGAUCUGGAAGCGGCUCAAUGACCAUGGCAAGAACUGGCGUCACGUUUACAAGGCCAUGACGCUGAUGGAGUACCUCAUCAAGACCGGCUCGGAGCGCGUGUCGCAGCAGUGCAAGGAGAACAUGUACGCCGUGCAGACGCUGAAGGACUUCCAGUACGUGGACCGCGACGGCAAGGACCAGGGCGUGAACGUGCGUGAGAAAGCUAAGCAGCUGGUGGCCCUGCUGCGCGACGAGGACCGGCUGCGGGAAGAGCGGGCGCACGCGCUCAAGACCAAGGAAAAGCUGGCACAGACCGCCACGGCCUCAUCAGCAGCUGUGGGCUCAGGCCCCCCUCCCGAGGCGGAGCAGGCGUGGCCGCAGAGCAGCGGGGAGGAGGAGCUGCAGCUCCAGCUGGCCCUGGCCAUGAGCAAGGAGGAGGCCGACCAGGAGGAGCGGAUCCGUCGCGGGGAUGACCUGCGGCUGCAGAUGGCAAUCGAGGAGAGCAAGAGGGAGACUGGGGGCAAGGAGGAGUCGUCCCUCAUGGACCUUGCUGACGUCUUCACGGCCCCAGCUCCUGCCCCGACCACAGACCCCUGGGGGGGCCCAGCACCCAUGGCUGCUGCCGUCCCCACGGCUGCCCCCACCUCGGACCCCUGGGGCGGCCCCCCUGUCCCUCCAGCUGCUGAUCCCUGGGGAGGUCCAGCCCCCACGCCGGCCUCUGGGGACCCCUGGAGGCCUGCUGCCCCUGCAGGACCCUCAGUUGACCCUUGGGGUGGGACCCCAGCCCCUGCAGCUGGGGAGGGGCCCACGCCUGAUCCAUGGGGAAGUUCCGAUGGUGGGGUCCCGGUCAGUGGGCCCUCAGCCUCCGAUCCCUGGACACCGGCCCCGGCCUUCUCAGAUCCCUGGGGAGGGUCACCUGCCAAGCCCAGCACCAAUGGCACAACAGCAGCCGGGGGAUUCGACACGGAGCCCGACGAGUUCUCUGACUUUGACCGACUCCGCACGGCACUGCCGACCUCCGGGAGCAGCGCAGGAGAGCUGGAGCUGCUGGCAGGAGAGGUGCCGGCCCGAAGCCCUGGGGCGUUUGACAUGAGUGGGGUCAGGGGAUCUCUGGCUGAGGCUGUGGGCAGCCCCCCACCUGCAGCCACACCAACUCCCACGCCCCCCACCCGGAAGACGCCGGAGUCAUUCCUGGGGCCCAAUGCAGCCCUCGUCGACCUGGACUCGCUGGUGAGCCGGCCGGGCCCCACGCCGCCUGGAGCCAAGGCCUCCAACCCCUUCCUGCCAGGCGGAGGCCCAGCCACUGGCCCUUCCGUCACCAACCCCUUCCAGCCCGCGCCUCCCGCGACGCUCACCCUGAACCAGCUCCGUCUCAGUCCUGUGCCUCCCGUCCCUGGAGCGCCACCCACGUACAUCUCUCCCCUUGGCGGGGGCCCUGGCCUGCCCCCCAUGAUGCCCCCGGGCCCCCCGGCCCCCAACACUAAUCCCUUCCUCCUAUAAUCCAGGGCGGAAGGGGGCCUGGCUCCAUCCGGCUGCCCCAUUCCGGCUCCCUGGGAGAUCAGUGUUGUGAGUGCAUGUGAAAUGGGGGAUCCCCACCCCCAGUGCCCUUCCCCUUCCUGGGGCCCACUCACACUACACCCUCUUCCUUUCCCACCCCACCUCCCCGGAGAGAAACUGGACAUGGGGCCUGGGGAGGGGAGCUGGCCAGAGGAGGACCCCUUUCCCGUGGCAUUAGAAGGGGGAGGGGUGGCUGGGGCCCCCACCCAUUCCCCCUCCCUCCAAACUCCCAACCCCCAGUCAGUGUUUGAGCCUCCUCGUUCCCCUCACGCACCCGCUCACGCACCCUCGGUGAAUCCUUGGUGAUGAUUUUGGCAACUUUGGGAAUAAAUGGCAAUUCCCACGGGCUUGGCACUCCCAGAUUCCCAUCUGUGAUUUCGUGUGUCCCCCAGAGCCCCUUCAUCCAGGGACCCAGGGCUCAGGUCACAUCUCUUUCUCGGGGGUGGCUGGCAACCAGCCCCUCUGUCUCAGAAGCCCUGAUUUCCCUGACCCUCCCAGGUCAAGGGAUGGCUGGGUUGAGGGUGGACUGUGCGAGGCCUGGCGGAGCUGUAGCCCACACAGGUCCAGGUGGUCGGGAGGCCACUCAUGGCCAGACGCUUCCGGUGCAGGAGGCCUUGCUCUUGUGUUGAGGGGACACCAGGAUGAGGUCAGAGAGUGCACUGGGGUUCAGGGAGGAGAAGAAUCCUGAGAGAUGGCACAUGUGCAACACAGGUCACCGUCGCCAUCGCCCGGGCCCACCGCAAGCAUCACUAAUCCAUCCCUGCACUCCUGGAAAGCCGGGUCAGCCUCUGCCGGCUGAGCUGAGUGGACCACCAGGCGCCUCCUGGUUGUCCUCUGUGUGCUGUUUUCCUCUGUGUGCUCUUGUCCUGGGCUGGACCACACCUGGUGAGACUAUCCGGGAGAAUCCUCGGGCCGCCUUGUGAGGGGGGUGUUGCUGUCAUCUCCAGGGCUAGGUGACAGCUUGUUGCAGGCCCCACAGCCAGGGCCUCAGGGAUGGGGAUCUGGCCAUGUCUGUUUUAAGCCGAACAGGCUGUUCUUCCAUGUGGAGUCUCCCUCCGUGAUCCCCUGGGGUCAAGUCCUGACGGCUGGGUUCGCUCCCUCAGUGACUCCGACAGCUCUUGUCUCAGAGGUGCUGGGGUGAAGGCUGUGUGGGGCCAGGCCCCUGGGGUCAGACUUCUUGCCCCUUCUGCCCGGGGGACGCUCUGGGCUCAGGGUGGGGCCAGACAGCUACAUCACAGGGACACUUGUUAUGGGUCGGGGUCCAGGGAGCACCCAGCCAGUGGAGUGUUGGAGGCCACUGAGAGGGACAUGACUGCGGUGUCCGAGCAGCGUCGUGGCCACCCUGUGUGCCCACUCCCUGGUGGACAGACCUACGUCACCUGGGGAUUGCAGAGCAAAAGGAGUGCUGUUGGGGUGAUGUGAGGUUGGGGUUCUGUUUCUUGCUGUGAAUUGGGUCAUGACCUGUGUCGGAGCGUUCUCUGGCCUCCACUUGCCCCUGCAGACCAGGGUGUCUGGAGGGUUGUCGGGGGCUUGAUGGAGGAAUUGCUGACCACACCAUGCAGGAAGAGGUGGGUCCCAGGGACACAGGAACUUUGGGGUCAGCCGGUUCCAGAUUCAGUUGCAGAGGAGCAUCCCCCUUGCUUAGCCAGGGAGGGGAAGCCCUCUUCUCACACCCGGCCUGGGUAUGUUGUGGGAGAGUCAUUUCCCAGGAGGAAAUGGGGACUGUUACCGGGGGAGGGGGUGCUGUCCCCAGGCAGCAGCAAGCGUCCCUUACGCUUGGGCUGUCCGAGACCCUGCUGCUCUAGGCGGUUGUGAUGGGGGAGCCCCACAGGGCACAGAGAGCCAGCUGAAGGCGGCAGCUCUGGGUGGGAUCACAUGGAAAGGGGAGGCGAGCCGAGCCUCCCUCUUGCCAAUCUUGGUCUCCCCACAGGGUCAUAGCUCCUGGGCCCCUCACUUGUCAGACCCUCCAUUCACCAAAUUAAGGAUAAGUUUCACGAUUUCGCACUGCGGAGCCUGCACUCCCUUUCUCUUCAAAAAAGCUGAGGACGAAGAUAAAAUGAUACAGUUGGAUUAGUCCAGUGGAGGGGUUAAAGGUGUGAGGCUUUAAUUCUCCCCACCAUUUCCUCAUUUGGCAAAACAGAGAAGACAGGAUUGAAAAACAAGACAAAAACCCAGAGGCUUGCACAUAAAUUUGGGGCUUAACUACAGCAUCUUCGGCAUCUUCUUUUCCCUACAGUGCGAAUUACAAAGUAGCACCACAGAUCUCGUGUCUCCUACUUUAUUCCUCUUUCUAGAAUAUUCCAGCCACCAAAGUGCUCAGCAGGAGCUGCUGUGUAGGAGUCCCCCAUGAGGCCCAAGCACCUGAGCUUAGUGACAUACACGGUUGAACGCUGGGAGAAUGCUGGGAGCCUGCUGUUGUCCCCGAUUGAGGGCUCCCCCCACUGUGUGUGUAUCACUCUUUCUACAGCAGAUGUGUCUCUCUCCCCACAGUGGGAUGGCGAGCUUGUUAAAUGGCCGUGAGGAAGACUUUAUUCAGGACCAUCGAGACAGGUACAGGUACCAUCAGUGGAUGGAAAAUCACUAAGAGCAAACCUCAGGGGUCCGGGGGUUUUCGGCUAAACCCACCUAGCAGGAUUCUUGCUGAAGGCAGGCCAGGGUGAUCAGAGGUCACCUGGGGAUGGUGGAGGCUGAAGAAGCCUAUCAGAUGUGAGGGUGGCGGGGGUUGGGGGGGAUGGCGGCGGGGUUCAUUUGCUGAAAGGAUUUUACAAGGGCAUGCACGGAUGGGCCUAGGAGGAGGUUCAGAUCCCUCAGGUUUGGCUAAGCAAGAGUCAUGGUGGUGCUCCCGGCUGGCUCUCAGGAGCAGAUGUGCUUCUGACCCGACGUCUUCCCCCAGAGAGGGCUGAAGUGGAAAAAACCCCAGAAUUUCUCCCUGGGACAGGUGAAGCGAUGGGGCGUGGGACAUUCCUGGGUCUCGACUCUGUUCAGGGCCUAGGGGUUGGGUGGGGAAGGCACUUGAGGGAACCUUCCUGGAGCCCGUAGGAGCUUCAUCCGAGCUCCUGGGUCACCCCGCCCACCAGAGUCCAGGCCCACCAGAGUCCCCUGCCACCUGUGCUCACCCUAGCCUUACCCCUCGCUCUACUCCCGCCCUCGCCCUAUCCUCGCUCCUCGCCCUACGCUUGCCCCUCGCUCUGGAGCUGCGAUGCCAGCCUCAGGGCUUUCAGUCCUGCCUUGAUCUUUUUUUAUACUGAAACUCAAUUUUACACACACAAACCCACUCCCAGCCAGCCUCUGCCUUUUGCCUUUUCCUCAUGUUCUCAUUGAAUAGGAAGAAAUGCCCUUUUUUUUCCCCCCUAGAAGGAGUCUUGCUCUGUUGCCAGGCUGGAGUGCAGUGGCACGAUCUCGGCUCACCGCAACCUCCACCUCCCGGGUUCAAGCGAUUCUCCUGCCUCAGCCUCUCGAGUAGCUGGGAUUACAGGUGCCCACCACCACGCCCAGCUAAUUUUUUUUUGUAUUUUUAGUACAGACGGGGUUUCACCAUGUUAGGAUGGUCUCGAUCUCCUGACCUCGUGAUCCGCCUGCCUCGGCCUCCCAAAGUGCUGGGAUUACAGGCGUGAGCCACUGUAGCGGCCCCCACCCCAUUUCAUUUUUUAUUUUUUUAUUAUACUUUAAGUUCUAGGGUACCUAUGCACAACGCGCAGGUUUGUUACAUAUAUAUACAUGUGCCAUGUUGGUGUGCUGCACGCAUUAACUCGUCAUUUACAUUAGGUAUAUCUCCUAAUGCCUUCCCUCCCGCCUCCCCCAGGCCCUUAGUUUGUGCUGCUCUGCGUUGGUUUUCUGCGUGUGCUAAAAGGGGAGGGAGAGUUUCUGUGCCCAUUCCCAGGCACCUUCUUGCAGCCGCAGGCAUCUCCCCCACACGUGCUUCUAGCUUCCCGGGUGUGGCGUGAGCCAUUGCGUCCGGCCAGAAAUGUUUUAUUUCUUGAGAACUUGUCUGUCUCUGUGAUGACUGUGGGUUGUCCAGCUCAUCCCUCAAGCGCCAUCCUGCCAGGCCCUUCACUGUGGUGAGAAACCGGCCUACUCACAUCACAGGUGCCCCUGGAGUUUCUCAAACUGCAGCCCAAGGAUUGGCUGCUUGCUUUUGUAAAAAAAAAUGUUUUAUUAGAGUGCAGCCACGGCUGCUUCUGCACUACAGUGGCAAUGGUGACAUUGAGUGUGGCAGAGACCGAGUGUCCCUUGAGCCUAAAAUAUUUACUAUCUGGCUCUUCAACAAAAAGUGUGCUGACCCCCGGUGAUUGCUUGUAUGUGGCAGGGGUCUAAGGCCUGCCUGCACGUCCUGGGACAGCCCACGCUUCCACAGGGUUCCAGCAUGCUUUCCGCCGAGAAAUCGCUCCCUUUGCUGUUUGUUUUGUAUUGAAUGUUUCUUCAUGCUUUUGUUUUACUUUCAGGGAUAAUUAUAUAAUGUUAUGUUUCAUCCACAUUAUUUUAGUAUGGAUAUUUAUAAUUUCCUAAAGCACUAUUUUUUUUUUUUGAGACAGAGUCUUGCUCUGUCGCCCAGGCUGGAGUGCAGUGGCUCGAUCUCUGCUCACUGCAAGCUCCGCCUCCUGUGUUCACGCCAUUCUCCUGCCUCAGCCUCCCAAGUAGCUGGGACUACAGAUGCCCACCACCAUGCCCAGCUAAUUUUUUUGUAUUUUUUUAGUAGAGACGGGGUUUCACUGUGUUAGCCAGGAUGGUCACGAUCUCCUGACCUCGUGAUCUGCCCACCUCGGCCUUCCAAAGUGUUGGGAUUACAGGCUUGAGCCACUGUGCCCGGCCCAUAAAGCACUAUUUAAUGACUGCUCCAUAAAUACAAACUUCCUUUCCUUAUUAUUAUUAUUUAUUUUUUUUUUGAGAUGGAGUCUUGCUCUCGUCCCCCAGGCUGGAGUGCAGUGGCGCGAUCUCGGCUCACUGCAACCUCCGCCUCCCGGGUUCAAGCGAUUCUCCUGACUUGGGACUACAGGUGCGUGCGACCACAGCCAACUCAUUUUUCUGUUUUUAGCAGAGACAGGGUUUCACCAUAUUGGCCAGGCUGGUCGAACUCCUGACCUUGUGAUCCACCCGCCUCGGCCUCCCAAAGUGCUGGGAUUACAGGCGUGAGCCACGGCACCCGGCCCAUAAUUACAAACUUUCUGAGGGACAUCUUGAAGCACACAAAACUAUAGACAAUAUUAUCAUAACCACCCCUGCAAAUGCCUCACUCGUGUUCAGCCAUCAUUUACAUUUGAACCACUCCUGUUUCACCUACAGCCUCCUCAUGGCCCCUCCCCUGGAGCACUUAAAAAUGGUAAUGACAUGCUCUCUAGUAAUCGUUGUGUGUUACUGUCAAAAGGUAUAACUCAUGCAUUGAUGGGGGUAACCCCUACAGCAGUUAACCCUGCGUGCUCAGAGGGGAAUGAAAGGUAGCUCAGAGGCUCGGGAGGUGAGGUUGCAAAAUGGCUUGUGUUGUGGGGAAUGUUCUCAUCCACCCAAAUCAAGCAUCACUACAUCCAUCCGCAGGGGAGGCAAGCUUAGGGCAUCACGUCCAGGAGUGGCCAGGUCCCGAUGUCACGGGGAGCCGGGCUGGGACAAGCUCCAGACGGCCAGGGUGGUGUGGGUUUGCAGUGGGAGGGCUGGCGCGGGGGCCCUGAGGGCUCCCUGGUUCCCAUCUUAUCAAGAUGCUGGACUCGGUGCUUGAAACAUGUCCUGACAGCCACAUGAAAAGGGUUAGAAAUGAUACUGUUUCGCCUGGGUGCUGUGGCUCAUGCUUGUAAUCCUAGCACUUUGGGAGGCCGAGGCGGGCGGAUCACGAGGUCAGGAGUUCGAGACCAGCCUGGCCAACAUGGCGAAACCCCGUCUCUACUAAAAAUACAAAAAUUAGCCUAGUGUGGUGGCGGGCACCUGUAAUCCCAGCUACUUAGGAGGCUGAGGCAGGAGAAUCGCUUGAACCCAGGAGGCGGAGGUUGUAGUGAGCCGAGAUUGCACUACUGCACUCCAGCCUGGGUGACAGAGUGAGACCCUGUCUCCAAAAAAAAAAAAAAAAUGAUACUGUUUCCUGUAUUUUUUUCUCUUAGUAUCUUAAGAAAUACAUGAUUUGAACAAGGACCUUGUGUCUCCUCUCCCCUUUCCCGGACUAUUCUGACCCCAGCAGUUCUCAGAAGGAGCUGACAUUAAUGAGAACUUCUCCCUGUUAGACCCUUAAAAUACUGAGCUUUCGGGACCCUGCCUGGCUUGUUCCUGUAAAACGGUCUUGUCUGUGGUAAAUACUAAGGUUUUUGGUCUCACAGCCGAGGAAAUCAAGGAUGUGGAUGCACACAGAGUGAGAUUUGGAGCAGGAGUUUAAUAGGCAAAAGGAAGAAACAGCUCUGUCACAGAGACGGGUCCCGAACGGGUUGUGAAGUUGUAGAAGAAAUGUCAGGGGUUUUAUAGAUGGGCUAGUGAGGAGGGGUGUCUUUUCUUCCUAGGGCCUGAAGAACCAGUUAGGACCAGGUGUGCUGUCUGCAUCGAGCAGAGUCUCUAGCAGCCCCCACCCCAUUCUUUUUUUUUUUUUUUUUUUUGAGAUGGAGUCUCGCUCUGUCGCCCAGGCUGGAGUGCAGUGGUGUCAUCUUGGCUCACUGCAACCUCCGCCUCCCAGGUUCAAGCAAUUCUCGUGCCUCAGCCUCCCGCGUAGUCGGGAUUACAGGUGCAUGCAGCCAUGCCCGGCUAAUUUUGUAUUUUUAGUAGAGACAAGGUUUCACCAUGUUGGUCAGGCUGGUCUCCAACUCCUGACCUCAAGUGAUCCGCCUGCCUCGGCCUCCCAAAGUAGUGGGAUUGCAGGCGUGAGCCACCGCGCCGGGCCCCCACCCCAUUCUUUGAUCCUGCAGGCAGGCCCUUCGUUUGUGCUGCUCUGCGCUGCUGCUUAUCUGUGUGUGCUAAAAGGGGAGGGAGUGUUUCUGUGCCCAUUCCCAGGCACCUUCGUGCAGCUGCAGGCAUCUCCCCCACGCGCUUCCAGCUUCCCUUAGUGUGCCUAAAGAAAGGGAAAGGAAUGUGCUUUAGGCCCACUGUUUUCACUGGGGCCCAUCUAUGUAUGUGGCUUGGUGAUUACCCAGGAACCUCCCAAGUCUGUGCCCGAGUUGCUUAUCUGUGUUUUACAGCCUGAAAGAUCAGGCUGCUCUUUGUUAGGAGAAGUGAUUUCUUUGAACUGCGUGGUGUGGUGAGAAAGGGAGCAAUUUCUAAGCUGCUUUUUGUUAGGAAGUUUUUUGCUGGGGACUCUCUUCGCCCUAUCUACCUAAAUGAUUUCUGUUUCUUACAUCAAUUGGGUAUUGAUUUCAGGUAGAAUGGGUGAAUGCAUUUAUUCGUUCAUCUAAGCCGCAUUUACUCCUUUCUUUUCUUUCACUGUUGUUUUUUUUUUGAGACGGAGUCUUGCACUGUCACCCAGGCUGGAGUGCAGUGGUGCGAUCUCGGCUCACUGCAAGCUCCACCUCCCGGGUUCAUGCCAUUCUCCUGCCUCAGCCUCCCGAGUAGCUGGGACUACAGGCGCCCACCACCACGCCCGGCUAAGCUAAUUUUUUGUAUUGUUAGUAGAGACGGGGUUUCACCGUGUUAGCCAGGAUGGUCUCAAUCUGACCUUGUGAUUCCGCCCACCUCGGCCUCCCAAAGUGCUGGGAUUACAGCCGUGAGCCACCGCACCUGGCCUCUUUCAGUUUUGAUAGCAGAUUAUUUCCUUUGGCCCUGCGUGGUCUCUCUCUGGCUGGGCAGCUCUGGGCCAGCCAUAAAUGGAGGGGAGGGCGUGUGUGUGGCCACGUGUGUUUCUGUCCUGGACAACACUGUCCGGAGGGGCCUAAGUGGGAAGUGCCCUCAACCAAGGAGAUAGCUGCUGUGUGUGUGUGUGUUGUGUGUGGUUGGGACAGUCGGGGAUUCUCACUUUUUUUUAAAAUUUGAGAUGGAGUUUCACUGUCGUCACCCAGGCUAGAGUGCAAUGGUGUGAUUUCGGCUCACUGCAACCUCUGCCUCCCGGGUUUAAGCGAUUCUCCUGCUUCAGCCUCUCAAGUAGCUGGGAUUACAGGUGCCCGCCACCACGCCCAGCUAAUUUUUGUAUUUUUAGUAGAGACGGGGUUUCACCACGUUGGCCAGGCUGGUCUGGAACUCCUGACCUCAGGUGAUCCACCUGCCUCGGCCCCCCAAAGUACUGGGAUUACAGGCGUGAGCCACUGGGCGCAGCCUGGGAUCCUCACUUUUUCGCAGAUUGGUCACUAGCAGGGCGUCUGAUGGAACUUUCUGAGAUGCCGGAAAUGUUCUCUGUGCUGUACAAAAGGGAUGCCACUAGCCACAUGCCACGUAGAACAGUUGAAAUGUGGCCAGCAUGAGAUUUUUUUAAUCUUGCCAAUUUUUGAUGGAUUUAAGUUUAAGCACCUGCGUGUGAGCGGCUACCGCGUGGGCUGGGAUUGGAGGAAGCUGGAAAGCGCUCCCCUGCGUUUCGGCUGCUGGCCCAGCAGAGGGCGCCGGAGAGCGGACGGAGCCGCAGGCGGGGUUGUGGGAAGACGCUGGGAUCCCGUGCGCGCUUGUGCUCCUUCCUUCUGGGCCAGCGCGCAGACUAUCAACCGAGGUAUUCAGUCCCUCGGAAACCCAGUUCCUCCGUUUCCAGGCUUCUCGCCCACACGGAGACAGUCGCUCUCACACGUACCUCUCGCGGGCUCUUACUCGUGGUCCCGGUCUCCUCCUGGUCCCCACCUUCCAGCCCAGCGCGCACACUAGACGGCACGUGCUCUCCACGCUCUUUCUCCAGCGCCCCUUGCUCACCCGCCCCCCGUUGGAGUGGCCCAUCCUCUCCGCUUAGACACCUGCAGUCACUGUCACUAGCUGAACUGCGCCCUCCUGAAAGCUCUAUGUUGAAACCCUACCCCCCACCCUGCACCGACCCCGUACCCCAGAAUGGGGCUGUAUUUGGAGACAGGGCCUUUACAAGGUAAGUAAGGUUAAAAUGAGGACAUUAGGGUGGGUCCUAAUCCAAUCUGACUGUUAUAUAGUGGGGUUGCACCUUCAUGUGAGGACGCCGGGAGAAGACAGCCGUCUGGGAGCCAAGGAGAGAGGCCUUGGCGGAAGCCAACCCUGCAGCACCUUCAUCUUGAAUUUCUGGUUUCCAGAACUGUGAGAAAAUCCAUUGACGUUCUAUAGCGCUCCCAGCUGGCGGUACUUUGUUAUGACAGCCCUAACAUGAAUGCAGCCAUCCACACUGUCUGGGGGAAGGCACACACACCCCACAGCACCCUUGCUGUCUCACCCCGUAUCGCAAAAGCUCACGCAUGUGUCUCUCCCGAGUCCCUGGAGGGUCCUGCCACCUACAUCUCUCUCCUUGGCCUGCCGCCUGUGAUGCUCCUGGGCCCCCUGCUCCAGCACCGCUCCCUUCCUUCUGUAAUACAGACAACAGAGACAGGAGAUGGCCUGGCCCCACUUCAUUUCUGUUCCCUGGGAAAUAAGCAUCGCAAGUGAUCCGUAGAAUGGUAGACAUCAUCCACUUCCCAAGCAUCUCUGGCUGAAUGCUGUUCUCAUCCACUUCCCAAGCAUCUCUGGCUGAAUGCUGUUCUACACAUGCACGUGGGAGGCACCAGGGAGCCCAGAAGAAAUGAAAAGCCUGGGCAGACUCGCAGUUCUGCCACACAGUGAAUGUGCUACUCAAGCCACUCAGCCUGGGCUGCAGAGGUUGGAAGCCUCACUGGCCUGAGGUUUCUGAGUAAGCUCUGACCCAAUCAUUGACUAUUAAACUUCAGAGGUCCAUGGAGACCUCUUAGGAGUCUUUGAAGGAACUUAGCAUAGAUACCGAUAGCUGCUGACUGCAGGGAGAUGGGGAGAUAUGUUUUGUAAACCUGUCCAGGCAACUUUUUUGCCUACGGAAACACACAAAAACGAAAACAAACCAAUGAAAAAAACCUCUCAGAACGAUACAGAAUCCAGAGCCACUACAACACAUUUCAUGAAGUGGCGUGAGCCUGUAAUUCCAGCAGUUUGGGAGGCCGGGGCGAAUGGAUGACUUGAGGUCAGGAGUUCGAGACCAGCCUGGCCAACAUGACAAAAUCACCAUCUCUACUAAAAAUACAAAAAUUAGUCAUGCAUAGUGGCAUGCACCUGUAGUCCCAGCUACUCGGGAUGCUGAGAUGGGAGAAUCGUUUGAGCCCGGGAGGUGGAGGUUGCAGUGAGCCGAGAUCGCACCAUUGCACUCCAGCAUGGACAACAGAGCAAGACCCUUUCUUAGAAAAAAGAAAAGUAUCCCCGAACAUUAUCAGAGUCAAGUUAAUAAAGGCCAAAGGUAGAGAAAAUCUUGAAAGUAUCGAGAAAAUGACAUGUCAAUCAUAAGGUCAGGUUCUUCAACAGUCAUACUGACAUUGUGGCUGGAAUAUUUGUUGUUGUGGGAUAUAUAUAUAUAUAUAUAUUUAGAGUGUUGUGGGAUAUAUAUAUAUAUUUAGAGACAAGGUCUUGCUCUAUCACUAAAGCUGCAUUGCAGUGUGUGAUCAUAGCUCACCAUGGGAUUCUUGAUUUUCAGUGAGUAUAAAGUGUAAGACAAAAUAAGUCUUAGUUCAGGUAUGCUGGAUGGGAAGCCAGAGGUCUGCAUAGCAGUUACAAAGAAGGCCUUAUUAUCUGGAAGAAAAGGGACCAUAGAAUGUCCAUUGGUUGGGGAACAACCCAGCUUUAGUUUUUCCAGAUUCUCUGCAUGUGCAGGUUUAUGAGACUGGAGAACUUUGAUUUCUUCUUCCUCCUCCUCCUCUCUUUUCUUCUUCCUCUUCCUCCUUUUUCUCCUCCUUUCUUCCUUUAUUUUUCUUUCUUCCUUUCCUCCUCUUUCUUCUCCUUUUUCCUCCUCUUUUCUUCCUUUCUUCUCUUUUUCUUCUUCUUUUUUUUUUUUUUUUAAAAGACCGUGUUUCGCUCUGUCACCCAGGCUGGAAUGCAGUGGCGUACUGUUUUAGAAAAGUGAAAGAGGGCCGGGCGUGGUGGCUCAUGUCUGAAAUCCUAGCACUUUGGGAGGCUGAGGCGGGUGGAUCACCUGAGGUUGGGAGUUCGAGACCAGCCUGGCCGACAUGGCAAAACCCUGUCUCUACUAAAAAUACAAAAAUUAGCCGGGCAUGAUGGCAGAUGCCUGUAAUCUCAGCUCCUCAGUAGGCUAAGGCGGGAGAAUCGCUUGAACCCAGAGGCAGAGGCUGCAGUGAGCCAAGAUUGCAGCAUUGCAGGAAAGAGAGAAAAAGGAGGGAAGGGGAAGGAAAAGGAAAGAAAGAAAAGAGGGGAAGGGAAGGGAGAGAUUUAAAAAACAAUAGUAAAGAGAGAUUUAAAAAACAAUAGUAAAGAGAGAUUAAAAAAAAAAAGUAAAUGGGCCAGGUGCGAUGGCUUGUGCCUGUAAUCCCAGCAGUUUGAGAGGCUGAAGUGGGAGGAUCACUUGAAGCCAGGAGUACCAGACCAGCCUGGGAAACAUAGUGAGACCCCGUCUAUACUAAAAAAUAUUUAAAUGGGCUGAGCGCGGUGGCUCAGGCCUGUAAUCCCAGCACUUUGGGAGGCCGAGGCAGGCGGAUUACCUCAGGUCAGGAGUUUGAGACCAGCCUGACCAACAUGGCAAAACCCCAUCUCUACUAAAAAUACCAAAACAAAAACUAGCAGGGCAUGGUGGCGCAUGCCUGAAAUCCCAGCUACUCAGGUGGCUGAGACAGGAGAAUCACUUGAACCCAGGAGACGGAGGCUGCAGUGAGCCGAGAUUGUGCCACUGCACUCCAGCCUGGGCGAGCAACAGAGUGAGGCUGUCUCUCAAAAAAAAAAAAAAAGGAACGGUAGUGUGCACCUGUGGUCCCAGCUACACAGGAGGCUGAGGCAGGAGCAUCACUUGAACCCAGGAGUUCAAGGCUGCAGUGAGCUAUGAUGGCACCACUGCCCUCCAGACUGAGCCAAAAAGCAGACCCUGACUCUAAAACAAAAGAAAGAACAAAUAACAAAUGAAAAUAAAUACCCAAAAACCAGUCAAAUGUGAAACUGGUGUCAGGGGUAUGUUCUCCAUGUUGAGCCCCUUCUGUGGAAUAUGACAGUGUCUCUAUUUCGGGUAAAGGAAAGACCAAAAUAACUUUCCAAGAUGAAAAGCUAAGAGUGCUGAUCUCAUCACAGACAUAGCCAGCUCUUCAGUUCAGACCACCUGGAAACCCUCCCCAUGUCUUUUCAGAACAAUGUCCUAAGAACCAUAGGGGAAGUGGCCAUAAAAACCAUCUUUCCUUUGCAGACUGGGGUGGGGACUCUGGCCAAUGCCAUUCUGUUCUUCCAUAAUAUCUUUCCCAUCUUGACUGAGCAUCAAAUGAGGCCCACACACAAGAUUCUCACCCACAUGGCCGUGGCAAACUCCUUGGUUCUUCUUUCCACUGGAAUCCCCCACACAAUGGUGUCUUUUGUCCUAUGGAAACCCUUGUCCAGUCUUGAGUGUAAACUCGUGUUUACAGGUCUUAAAGUCCUGACCUGGUGAUCCGCCCGCGUGGACCUCCCAAAGUGCUGGAAUUACAGGCGUGAGCCACCACUCCUGGCCUAUGCCAGCAUUCUUUAAAGUUGUGGGAAAAGGCCAAAAGCAAAUAGAAAAUUGGGCAAAAAAGUUCAUAAUUGCUUAAACAUAUGGAAAACCUGGAAGUAAAAUUAAGCAAGUAAGUGCGAGCACUCUACAUUGAAGAUUAUAGAAAAUUCAGCCUCCCAAAUAUCCAAAGAAUCCAGGAGUGUGCCAAGAGAUCCAAGAGUAGGUCCACAAUUUCUCAUUCUCAGGAGAAUCUGAGAUUAUAUUUCAAUCUAAUGAUAACUGAUUAUAUAAUCCAAUUUCUGCAUCAUCUUGCUUUUAUGUUUUGUAAUAAAAAUUUUAGACCAGGCCAAUAAGGCAUCAGCAAUUUACCGUAGGGAACUAGGGAAUGUUUAAUUAUGACAAUGAAGUGUUUAAUAUUGUGUUUUGAAAUAUAAACAGUGUAGAUAUAUUUGAAUAAUACUGAAUUUUUAGAAAAAUCUAUUGGGGUGUCAUAUAUAAAAGGAUAAGUAGAGAUUUGGAAAUGCUUUUUUAUUGGACAAGAAAAUUGAUCAAAUCGAAAUCUGGACAAACUAGAAAGUCUGGAUGCUAGCAAUACAAUCUAUAGACACAUUCUAGCAUCACUUCUGUGUCAGAAGUAUCCGGAUUGUGGUGCCUACAAAUGCAUGCUCCUACACACCAAGACAUCCAUUAAGAAAAUAAAGCCAUGCUUUCCAGAGCGUUUAGCACUUGUUUAACGUACUUGUGCUUCUAAAUAUCACAAGGCAGGAUGGGAUUUCUAAAGACAAGGGGAUAUAGGACCGAGGCAAAGACAAUCAGCAUGUACACUGAAUCACACUCCAUAAUCAUAUUGCUAGAACACUUAGGGAGUACCUCUGAAAUCACAGCCCUGCUGCCAUGAUGUGCAAUUACAGGAUAGAGGUGCCAGGUGAAGGUCCCACUGUGGCCAAGGAAAGCCUUUGUGAGACGACUACUUCAGGGUGUUCCCCAUCAGAGGAGCACACCCCUGAUCUUGUAUUCCUCGUCAAUCCAAGGUCCAUGUGAAAUGGUCAGAUGGGGAAUUUUUUCUUCCACAGACAUCAGGAUCUUCUGAGUUUCUUCAUCAAAGCCAGAUUUGUGCAGCCUGGGAAAAUAGAAAUAAAGUUUUUUUUUUUGUUUUUCAUUUUUACACAGUAUUGCCUCUCUACAUUCUGAUGUCUACCUCUCCUCUCCUCUUUAUUCUUUCCUAGAAAUCACUGGGAGAAUUGUACUGAAUUUGAAAAACAAGCAUGAAUCUUUCCUAUAGGAUAGGAAGCCUCUGAUUUAUACCAUAAAGUGAAAUUUCAUAUACAGGAUGUAUCAAUUAAGAUUUAAUUCAAAAAAGAUGAAUUUAAGUUAAAAAGAAAAACACAGGAUAACUUCCAUUCAUCUGAUGUUCAUAUGCCCUGGCACAUCUAUUGCUUCUUAUAAUGUGCUUGCUUAAAAAAAAAAAACAUGAGCUUUUCUCAGAGACACUAAUAUAAUGAAUUCAUGUACCCAUCACCAACUUCUACAAUUACCAAUAUUCAGCCUCUUCCAUUUACAACCUGCCCAUUUUCUAAGAAAUAAUUAAAGCACAUGCUACACCCAUAAA